GCAGUCCCAGCCGCCUUCCCCAGGCAGUGGAACCUUCGGGCUCCUGAGCUUCAGGAUGGUUCGUACUAAGACAUGGACCCUGAAGAAGCACUUUGUUGGCUAUCCUACUAAUAGUGACUUUGAGUUGAAGACAGCUGAGCUCCCACCCUUAAAAAAUGGAGAGGUCCUGCUUGAAGCUUUGUUCCUCACCGUGGAUCCCUACAUGAGAGUGGCAGCCAAAAGAUUGAAGGAAGGUGAUACAAUGAUGGGGCAGCAAGUGGCCAAAGUUGUGGAAAGUAAAAAUGUAGCCCUACCAAAAGGAACUAUUGUACUGGCUUCUCCAGGCUGGACAACGCACUCCAUUUCUGAUGGGAAAGAUCUGGAAAAGCUGCUGACAGAGUGGCCAGACACAAUACCACUGUCUUUGGCUCUGGGGACAGUUGGCAUGCCAGGCCUGACUGCCUACUUUGGCCUACUUGAAAUCUGUGGUGUGAAGGGUGGAGAAACAGUGAUGGUUAAUGCAGCAGCUGGAGCUGUGGGCUCAGUCGUGGGGCAGAUUGCAAAGCUCAAGGGCUGCAAAGUUGUUGGAGCAGUAGGGUCUGAUGAAAAGGUUGCCUACCUUCAAAAGCUUGGAUUUGAUGUCGUCUUUAACUACAAGACGGUAGAGUCUUUGGAAGAAACCUUGAAGAAAGCGUCUCCUGAUGGUUAUGAUUGUUAUUUUGAUAAUGUAGGUGGAGAGUUUUCAAACACUGUUAUCGGCCAGAUGAAGAAAUUUGGAAGGAUUGCCAUAUGUGGAGCCAUCUCUACAUAUAACAGAACCGGCCCACUUCCCCCAGGCCCACCCCCAGAGAUUGUUAUCUAUCAGGAGCUUCGCAUGGAAGCUUUUGUCGUCUACCGCUGGCAAGGAGAUGCCCGCCAAAAAGCUCUGAAGGACUUGCUGAAAUGGGUCUUAGAGGGUAAAAUCCAGUACAAGGAAUAUAUCAUUGAAGGAUUUGAAAACAUGCCAGCUGCAUUUAUGGGAAUGCUGAAAGGAGAUAAUUUGGGGAAGACAAUAGUGAAAGCAUGAAAAAGAGGACACAUGGAAUCUGGAGGCCAUUUAGAUGAUUAGUUAAUUUGUUUUUCACCAUUUAGCAAAAAUGUAUACUACCUUAAAUGUCUUAAGAAAUAGUACUCAUAAUGAGUUUGAGCUACUUAAUAAAAUACAUUUAAGUGGUAUGUAAUUAGUGAUGGAGGAUGGAAGUUUCAAAGUCAACAACAACCAGUCACCUCACUGUUCACUACAGCUUCUUCUGAGUUGUGGUAGAAAAUAAUGGCUUUGAAGUGUGAAAAUUUUCCAAACACUGUAUGUUUUCAUUCAUAAGUGGGAGCUGAACAAUGAGAACACAUGGACAUAGGGAGGGGAACAACACACGCUGGGGCCUGUGGAAGCCGGGGUGAGGGAGGGAGAGCAUCAGGAUAAAUAGCUAAUGCCUUCGGGGGCUAAUACCUAGGUGAUGGGUUGACAGGUGAAGCAAACCAUCAUGGCACACGUUUACCUAUGUAACAAACCUGCACAUUCCACACAAUUAUCCCGGAACUGAAAAUAAAAUAAAAUUAAAUUAAAAAAAAAAGUUAGCCGGG